GAGAGACACCUCCCCUCCUUCCUUCAUCAAGACAUCAAGGAGGGACCUGUGCCCUGCUCCACAUCCUCCCACCUGCCGCCCGCAGAGCCUGCAGGCCCCGCCCCCCUCGUCUCUGGUCCCUACCUCUCUGCUGUGUCUUCAUGUCCCUGAGGGUCUUGGGCUCUGGGACCUGGCCCUCAGCCCCUAAAAUGUUCCUCCUGCUGACAGCACUUCAAGUCCUGGCUAUAGCCAUGACACAGAGCCAAGAGGAUGAGAACAAGAUAAUUGGUGGCCAUACGUGCACCCGGAGCUCCCAGCCGUGGCAGGCGGCCCUGCUGGCGGGUCCCAGGCGCCGCUUCCUCUGCGGAGGCGCCCUGCUUUCAGGCCAGUGGGUCAUCACUGCUGCUCACUGCGGCCGCCCGAUCCUUCAGGUUGCCCUGGGCAAGCACAACCUGAGGAGGUGGGAGGCCACCCAGCAGGUGCUGCGCGUGGUUCGUCAGGUGACGCACCCCAACUACAACUCCCGGACCCACGACAACGACCUCAUGCUGCUGCAGCUACAGCAGCCCGCACGGAUCGGGAGGGCAGUCAGGCCCAUUGAGGUCACCCAGGCCUGUGCCAGCCCCGGGACCUCCUGCCGAGUGUCAGGCUGGGGAACUAUAUCCAGCCCCAUCGCCAGGUACCCCGCCUCUCUGCAAUGCGUGAACAUCAACAUCUCCCCGGAUGAGGUGUGCCAGAAGGCCUAUCCUAGAACCAUCACGCCUGGCAUGGUCUGUGCAGGAGUUCCCCAGGGCGGGAAGGACUCUUGUCAGGGUGACUCUGGGGGACCCCUGGUGUGCAGAGGACAGCUCCAGGGCCUCGUGUCUUGGGGAAUGGAGCGCUGCGCCCUGCCUGGCUACCCCGGUGUCUACACCAACCUGUGCAAGUACAGAAGCUGGAUUGAGGAAACGAUGCGGGACAAAUGAUGGUCUUCACGGUGGGAUGGACCUCGUCAGCUGCCCAGGCCCUCCUCUCUCUACUCAGGACCCAGGAGUCCAGGCCCCAGCCCCUCCUCCCUCAGACCCAGGAGUCCAGG